UCUGAGGUCCGAGACCCGAGUCCUGGCACUGGAGUUUGCUGACUCCCUCUGGUUUCCGGUCAGGUCGGUCGGUCCCCACUAUGGGCCUGGAGCUGUACCUGGACCUGCUGUCCCAGCCCUGCCGCGCUGUUUACAUCUUUGCCAAGAAGAACGACAUUCCCUUCGAGCUGCGCAUCGUGGAUCUGAUUAAAGGGGCCCUUCCAGUCUUUGCCAACCAGGAGUGCAGACUGGUGGGAAGAAGAACUGUGAAACUGGGGCCAGAGCAUUGCAGGGAGGGGCACAGGCCAUGGCGGGCUCAGCGUUCUCCUCCCACCACCCACCAUGCUGGACUCUUCCCAGGUCAGCACUUAAGCGAUGCCUUUGCCCAGGUGAACCCCCUCAAGAAGGUGCCAGCCUUGAAGGACGGGGACUUCACCUUGACGGAGAGUGUGGCCAUCCUGCUCUACCUGACGCGCAAAUAUAAGGUCCCUGACUACUGGUACCCUCAGGACCUGCAGGCCCGUGCCCGUGUGGAUGAGUACCUGGCAUGGCAGCACACGACUCUGCGGAGAAGCUGCCUCCGGGCCUUGUGGCAUAAGGUGAUGUUCCCUGUUUUCCUGGGUGAGCCAGUAUCUCCCCAGACACUGGCAGCCACCCUGGCAGAGUUGGAUGUGACCCUGCAGUUGCUCGAGGACAAGUUCCUCCAGAACAAGGCCUUCCUUACUGGUCCUCACAUCUCCUUAGCUGACCUCGUAGCCAUCACGGAGCUGAUGCAUCCCGUGGGUGCUGGCUGCCAAGUCUUCGAAGGCCGACCCAAGCUGGCCACAUGGCGGCAGCGCGUGGAGGCAGCAGUGGGGGAGGACCUCUUCCAGGAGGCCCAUGAGGUCAUUCUGAAGGCCAAGGACUUCCCACCUGCAGACCCCACCAUAAAGCAGAAGCUGAUGCCCUGGGUGCUGGCCAUGAUCCGGUGAGCUGGGAAACCUCACCCUUGCACCGUCCUCAGCAGUCCACAAAGCAUUUUCAUUUCUAAUGGCCCAUGGGAGCCAGGCCCAGAAAGCAGGAAUGGCUUGCCUAAGACUUGCCCAAGUCCCAGAGCACCUCACCUCCCGAAGCCACCAUCCCCACCCUGUCUUCCACAGCCGCCUGAAAGCCACAAUGAGAAUGAUGCACACUGAGGCCUUGUGUCCUUUAAUCACUGCAUUUCAUUUUGAUUUUGGAUAAUAAACCUGGGCUCAGCCUGAGCCUCUGCUUCUAACUCUAA